CCAUUUGACCGGUCCCAGGCCAGGACACACUCUUCCAUGCUCUGGCUGUGCUGUGCUAGAGGCUGAUAAUUUUUCUCCAGGUAGAGUAAAAGAUCAAGGCACGAACUAUAUAGAUUUACAGAAAAUAGGCCAAAGAUUGAGAUUUUUUUGACACAAGCAAGUCCAGAGAACUUUUACCAUGUAUGGUUACCGGCGCUUAAGAAGCCCCAGAGAUUCCCAGACAGAACCGCAGAAUGACAAUGAAGGAGAGACCAGUUUGGCUACCACACAAAUGAAUCCACCCAAACGUCGCCAAGUGGAGCAGGGUCCCAGUACAGGUGCAAAAAAACCCUCAAUUUCAGGAGCUCCACACCUGAAUUCAUACCAGUCCCUGGAACUUCCCCAGAAGCAGCAGGAUUCUGGCACUGAGGAGCUCAUGAUAGUCCUGGAACAAGGGACAGAAGUGAGGUUGAGCCUGGAAGAGGUCAUCCUCAUCUUGGCCCCAGAGACAGUGCUGCAGCUGACCCUGGAGAACACAGUCCUUGUGAUUGUCCCUGAGCAUGUCCUGAGGUCAGAAGAUGGCCUGCAGUCCCCUGUGCAGAUCCAGUACAUCAUACCUUCCGUUGAUGACUUCAGCUUGGAGUUCCAUGCUCAAGAUGGAGACAUCUCAGACAUGAGAAGAGAGAAUGUGCCUUUUUCACCUGCAGAAGAAGGGAAGGCAGCACCCCUGUAUCAGCAGCCCUUGAUGAUACCCCAAGCAAACCACAUGGCUGGGAUCAGCCCUUCUUUCCUAGUAACCCCAUUGUGCAUUCCACGCUGUCGGGCAGCCUUCCCCCAAUGCUACCCUCUACCACCCACACCUAGUCCCGUGGGACGCCCUAGACCAGCCGACUCCAGUUUCAGCCUGCAUGGUAUGGAGCUCUUGUGCACCUCCUCCCUCAGACCUAUGCCCCCUUCACCAAGUCCUGGUCCCCAGGUCUAUCACAUUCACCAUAGGCCUCCCAGCAGGGCACGGAGAUGUCUCUUUAGGAAGUGAUUUAACCCAAGAGCCACCCCCUGCAUUGAUAGGUCAGAGAUUGUCCAGAUCCUUAGUCAGUGCAUUCUCUGAAAUGUGGAGAGAAAGUAAUUUGACCACUUGCUUGCCCUUUGCUGUUCCCCAUCAUCAACCACUGUCUUCAACAGCGGAGGGUCCCAGAUGCUGCAGGGAGGGGGAGAACUGCAGGGAGUUCAAAUAAAACAUUCACAUUUCACUUCACACACACUGUCCCUUAGACUUUCUCUUCCUAUUUAAGCACAUACAUCCAACCACACUCAAUCAAAUCCCUGACUGCUCCAUGUGAGAGUUCUGCUUCCAGCAUGACGUGGUCUGAAAGUUCAUCUGAAGACAGCUGCUCACUCCCGGGGGCUAACACCGCCCCUUGCAUGCUGAUGUCCUUGUAGUCAUUGGUCUGAUGCCACAAUAAAUAAUUCCUAAGGCUGGUGCUCUAUUUCUGCCCUGAGACUCUCCCCUUUUUCUCCAAGCUGUGCCCCAUUCCUUGUCUUAGUCCAGGUUCCCUACACUCCCCAGGCCAAUGCUUUUGAAUAAAUCUUGACGUCAUUGAAUGAA